GAGCGAAUCUCGGAGUCGGUGGGUGCAGAUGGCGGCGGCAGUUGUGGUGGCGGAGGGGGACAGCGACUCCCGGCCCGGACAGGAGUUGUUAGUGGCCUGGAACACCGUGAGCACCGGCCUGGUGCCGCCGGCUGCGCUGGGGCUGGUGUCUUCCCGGACCAGCGGUGCAGUCCCGCCAAAGGAAGAGGAGCUCCGGGCGGCGGUGGAGGUUCUGAGGGGCCACGGGCUACACUCGGUCCUGGAGGAGUGGUUCGUGGAGGUGCUGCAGAACGAUCUGCAGGCCAACAUCUCCCCUGAGUUCUGGAAUGCCAUCUCCCAAUGCGAGAACUCUGCGGAUGAGCCCCAGUGCCUUUUGCUACUCCUUGACGCUUUUGGCCUGCUGGAGAGCCGCCUGGAUCCCUACCUGCGUAGCCUAGAGCUGCUGGAGAAAUGGACUCGCCUGGGCUUGCUGAUGGGCACUGGUGCUCAGGGGCUGCGAGAAGAAGUCCACACUAUGUUGCGCGGAGUCUUGUUCUUUAGCACCCCCAGAACCUUCCAAGAGAUGAUCCAGCGUCUGUAUGGGUGCUUCUUGAGAGUCUAUAUGCAGAGUAAGAGGAAGGGGGAAGGGGGCACAGACCCGGAACUGGAAGGGGAGCUGGACAGCCGGUAUGCCCGUCGCCGGUACUACCGGCUCCUGCAGAGCCCGCUGUGUGCAGGGUGCAGCAGUGACAAGCAACAGUGCUGGUGUCGCCAGGCUCUGGAGCAGUUCCAUCAGCUCAGCCAGGUCUUACACAGGCUCAGUCUGCUGGAGCGGGUCAGUGCCGAGGCUGUGACCACCACCCUGCACCAGGUGACCCGGGAGAGGAUGGAGGACCGUUGCCGGGGCGAGUACGAGCGCUCCUUCCUGCGUGAGUUCCACAAGUGGAUCGAGCGGGUGGUCGGCUGGCUCGGCAAGGUGUUCCUGCAGGACGGCCCCGCCAGGCCCGCAUCUCCCGAGGCCGGCAACACCCUGCGCCGCUGGCGCUGCCACGUGCAAAGGUUCUUCUACCGCAUCUACGCCAGCCUGCGCAUCGAGGAGCUCUUCAGCAUCGUCCGAGACUUCCCAGACUCCCGGCCAGCCAUCGAGGACCUCAAGUACUGCCUGGAGAGGACGGACCAGAGGCAGCAGCUGCUCGUGUCCCUCAAGGCUGCCCUGGAGACUCGGCUCCUGCAUCCAGGCGUCAACACGUGUGACAUCAUCACCCUCUAUAUCUCUGCCAUCAAGGCGCUGCGCGUGCUGGACCCUUCCAUGGUCAUCCUGGAGGUGGCCUGUGAGCCUAUCCGCCGCUACCUGAGGACGCGGGAGGACACAGUGCGGCAGAUUGUGGCUGGGCUGACGGGGGACUCGGACGGGACAGGGGACCUGGCUGUUGAGCUGUCCAAGACCGACCCGGCGAGCCUGGAGACAGGCCAGGACAGUGAGGAUGACUCAGGCGAGCCAGAGGACUGGGUCCCGGACCCUGUGGAUGCCGAUCCAGGGAAGUCGAGCUCCAAGCGGCGUUCAUCGGACAUCAUCAGCCUGCUGGUCAGCAUCUACGGCAGCAAGGACCUCUUCAUCAAUGAGUACCGCUCGCUGCUGGCCGACCGCCUGCUGCACCAGUUCAGCUUCAGCCCCGAGCGGGAGAUCCGCAACGUGGAGCUGCUGAAGCUGCGCUUUGGCGAGGCCCCAAUGCACUUCUGUGAAGUCAUGCUGAAGGACAUGGCGGACUCCCGCCGCAUCAAUGCCAACAUCCGGGAGGAGGAUGAGAAGCGGCCAGCAGAGGAGCAGCCACCGUUCGGGGUCUACGCUGUCAUCCUGUCCAGUGAGUUCUGGCCGCCCUUCAAGGACGAGAAGCUGGAGGUCCCCGAGGAUAUCAGGGCAGCCCUGGAGGCUUACUGCAAGAAGUAUGAGCAGCUCAAGGCCAUGCGGACCCUCAGUUGGAAGCACACCCUGGGCCUGGUGACCAUGGACGUGGAGCUGGCCGACCGCACGCUGUCUGUGGCGGUCACCCCAGUACAGGCGGUGAUCUUGCUGUAUUUUCAGGACCAAGCCAGCUGGACCCUGGAGGAACUGAGCAAGGCGGUGAAGAUGCCCGUGGCGCUGCUGCGGCGGCGGAUGUCCGUGUGGCUGCAGCAGGGUGUGCUGCGUGAGGAGCCCCCCGGCACCUUCUCUGUCAUUGAGGAGGAGCGGCCUCAGGACCGGGACAACAUGGUGCUCAUUGACAGUGACGACGAGAGCGACUCCGGCAUGGCCUCCCAGGCCGACCAGAAGGAGGAGGAGCUGCUGCUCUUCUGGACGUACAUCCAGGCCAUGCUGACCAACCUGGAGAGCCUCUCACUGGAUCGUAUCUACAACAUGCUCCGCAUGUUUGUGGUGACUGGGCCUGCACUGGCCGAGAUUGACCUGCAGGAGCUGCAGGGCUACCUGCAGAAGAAGGUGCGGGACCAGCAGCUCGUCUACUCGGCCGGCGUCUACCGCCUGCCCAAGAACUGCAGCUGACACAUCGCCCGCCCGCCCGCCCGCCCGCCAGGCGCUGCCCUGCAGGUGCUCUCGUCCUCCCGUGCCAGCCCCCGCCCGCCCGUGUCCCAGAAUGCACUGCUGAGGAGCAUGCCCACCCCCACCCCCGCAGUGUGCAGAUUAAAGCAAGUCAGAUCAUC